UUGCCAGGUAUAAACUCCGAAUUGUUAAGCCACCAAAAUUACCCCUAGAGAAAAAACCCAACCCUGAUAAGGAUGGUCCAGAUUAUGAGCCCAACCUCUGGAUGUGGGUAAAUCCCAACAUUGUGUAUCCCCCUGGAAAGCUGGAGGUCUCAGGACGUAGGAAGAGGGAGGACCUGACAAGCACACUCCCCUCCUCUCAGCCACCCCAGAAGGAGGAAGAUGCCAGCUGCUCAGAGGCCGCAGGGGUGGAAUCACUGUCCCAGUCCUCCAGCAAGCGGUCUCCCCCUCGGAAGCGGUUUGCCUUUUCCCCCAGCACCUGGGAGCUCACAGAAGAGGAGGAGGCUGAGGACCAGGAAGACAGCUCCUCUAUGGCUCUCCCAUCCCCUCACAAAAGGGCCCCCCUCCAGAGUCGGAGGCUUCGGCAAGCCAGCAGCCAGGCGGGGAGGCUCUGGUCCCGGCCCCCUCUCAAUUACUUCCACCUAAUUGCCCUGGCAUUAAGAAACAGUUCCCCCUGUGGCCUCAACGUGCAACAGAUCUACAGUUUCACUCGAAAGCACUUCCCCUUUUUCCGGACGGCCCCGGAAGGCUGGAAGAAUACUGUCCGUCACAAUCUCUGUUUUCGAGACAGCUUUGAGAAAGUGCCUGUCAGCAUGCAGGGCGGGGCCAGCACACGGCCUCGAUCUUGCCUCUGGAAGUUGACCGAGGAGGGACACCGCCGCUUUGCGGAGGAGGCCCGCGCCUUGGCUUCCACUCGGCUAGAAAGUAUCCAACAGUGCAUGAGCCAGCCAGAUGUGAUGCCCUUCCUCUUUGAUCUUUAACCCCAAGAAGCAACAGCCAGCUAAUGCUUUAUUAAAAUUACCCUCACUAGC